ACAAGAUCAUGGCCACUAACUACAGUGCCAACCAGUAUGAAAAGGCUUUCUCAUCCAAGUAUCUGCAGAACUGGUCUCCCACUAAGCCAACAAAAGAGAGCAUCUCUUCUCAUGAAGGCUACACUCAAAUUAUUGCCAACGAUCGUGGUCAUCUACUGCCUUCUGUGCCCCGUUCCAAGGCAAAUCCUUGGGGUUCCUUCAUGGGCACCUGGCAAAUGCCUCUGAAGAUACCCCCUGCUCGGGUGACCCUGACCUCCCGUACAACUGCUGGUGCUGCCUCCCUCACCAAAUGGAUACAGAAAAAUCCUGAUUUACUCAAGGCCUCCAAUGGGCUGUGUCCUGAAAUCUUAGGCAAGCCCCAUGAUCCAGACAGUCAGAAGAAACUCAGAAAGAAGUCUAUCACAAAGACUGUACAACAAGCACGAAGUCCAACCAUAAUUCCAAGCUCCCCAGCUGCCAACCUCAAUUCCCCAGAUGAACUCCAAAGCUCACACCCCUCUGCAGGUCAUACUCCAGGUCCCCAAAGACCAGCCAAAUCCUAAGAGCCCACCUGGAAGUCCACGUAUGCUAGAACUCUGGGCAGGGCCUAAUCUAGCUGAGGUCCAGAAAUACAAACCUGGAACUUCAUAUGGACCAAGUGGCCACACACUGAAAAACCCGUAUAGCGACUCAGUGAAAUAAACAAGAGCCCCCAGUCAGAACUGUGAAACAGGGAAAUUUUGGGGUGGGAGUAAAAGCAAAUUUGGAAAAUAAACUUUUUUUUGUUGAAUCUUU